GGCUGCAGUCUGCAUCAGCCUAUGCUAAGAAAAGAGAGACAACUCCUGCAUCUGGAAAUUCCUUCUCUCAGGGGCUGCUGGUGGGAGCAAGAUCCUCAGCUCUGGCCUUCAAAAGCUCCUGUGAUCUCUGCACAAUUUCUCUAAAUAGAAUUAUAUUUCUGAGACAAGACCAGGCCUGAUACCACACACAUAGCUCAUUGCCACAGCAGAGUCCAACGCAGGUACUGUCACAAGGGCAUGACAAAAAAUCAGACAUGGGUCACAGAAUUCAUUCUCCUGGGAUUUCCACUCAGCCUAAGGAUUCAGAUGCUCCUCUCUGGGCUUUUCUCCCUGUUAUACGUCUUCACCCUGCUGGGAAAUGGGGCCAUCCUGGGGCUCAUCUGGCUGGACUCCAGACUGCACACCCCCAUGUACUUCUUUCUCUCACACCUGGCCAUCAUUGAUAUUUCGUAUGCUUCCAACAAUGUCCCCAAGAUGCUGACAAACCUUGGCUUGAACAAGAGAAAAACAAUCUCCUUUGUCCCAUGCACAAUGCAGACCUUUUUAUACAUGGCUUUUGCUCACACUGAGUGUCUCAUCUUGGUAAUGAUGUCCUACGAUCGGUACAUGGCUAUCUGCCACCCUCUGCAAUAUUCUGUCAUCAUGAGAUGGGGAGUGUGCACAGUCCUGGCUGUCACUUCUUGGGCAUGUGGUUCCCUUCUGGCCCUGGUCCAUGUGGUUCUCAUCCUGAGGCUGCCCUUCUGUGGGCCCCAUGAAAUCAACCACUUCUUCUGUGAAAUCCUGUCUGUCCUCAAGUUGGCCUGUGCUGACACCUGGCUCAACCAGGUGGUCAUCUUUGCUGCUUCAGUGUUCAUCCUGGUGGGGCCGCUCUGCCUGGUGCUGGUCUCCUACUCGCGCAUCCUGGCGGCCAUCUUGAGGAUCCAGUCUGGGGAGGGCCGCAGAAAGGCCUUCUCCACCUGCUCCUCCCACCUUUGCAUGGUGGGACUCUUCUUUGGCAGCGCCAUUGUCAUGUACAUGGCCCCCAAGUCCCGCCACCCUGAGGAGCAGCAGAAGGUCCUUUCCCUGUUUUACAGCCUUUUCAACCCGAUGCUGAACCCCUUGAUCUAUAGCCUGAGGAACGCAGAGGUCAAGGGUGCCCUGAAAAGAGUGUUGUGGAAACAGAGAUCAAAGUGAGGGAUGCCAGGGAAAGUCUAGAGGGUUGAAGAUUUGCUCCCAAUGAGAUUUGUAGGAACAGUGGUGUAAAUGCCUUACAGUCUCAUCUCUUAGAUUUCUGAUAUCAAGAAUGUAUAUUGAUUGGAUUCUAUCCCUAAACGUGGAGUACCAUGCAGAUCACAAAGCACAUGCAGACAGGCGCUGAGCCGUGUGGUGCAGCAGAGGUGCAAAGUGCCAUGAACUCCUACUCCCAGGUCCCACCCCUACCCAGGAUCUGCUUUCUGUUCUUUUGAGGCUUAGUUCUCUCAAGCUUCCUCUUAAAUUCCUCUAUUAUUUCCAUCUCUUUUUGCCAUAAGUAUAUGCUGGUAAUCCCAUACCAUAUGCUACUAUAAGAGAGUACUUGUAAUCACACAGAAUAAAUACUGACCUUGGUUAAGCAGCCCUCUACUGGGAAUGUAACAACAACUAAGAGUAUAGAAAAUGCCUGGUUUGGAACCUAAAGCCUAAGGAUGAUGAUAUUAGUACUGGAAGUUCAUCUAAAUCACCCUAACAAAUCUAAUUCUGUAAAAAGCAAAGUUUAAUUGUAUAGAUUUUUUUAUAUAAAAGGCAGAGAAAUAUCAGGAUCUUUGUUUCAUUUCACUUAAUUCUGCACCAUUUAAUUAGAAAGAGUUUGGAAAGAUUUUGCAUUUAAAAUAAAUAUGAGAGAAUGUUAUUAGGGAUAGUUACCUUUUUCAUAAUUCAGAUCGCAAAGCCGGGUGUAGGUGACAAUUUAUCAUUACGGUGAUUACAUAAAAUAUUGUAGUAGUAAGAAAAUACUGCAAAGGAAGAAAGCAUCAAGGGAAACUGACAGCUUGAUGUAACAUCAUAGACCACCGCUUAGAACCAAGAACAUGUCAAGUCUUGAUAAAGACUUUCAGGAACCUCAACAAAAUUCCAAAGAGAAGCUAUUCCAGGUGACAUAAAUCACUUUUCCUGGACCCAAGUGGUCAGAAUGACAUGGACAGGUAAUUUGUUUUAUUUUAACACAAGUCUGAGUCCUAAAUGAUCAGCAUAAUAUGAUAAUAUGAUUUCUUUAACACAUUGAGUAUGGUACCUUUUGGAAUUCUCUCUUUUUUCUCUCAACCCUUGUAGUAUUGUGUGAAUUCAACUGUAUGACCCAUGAUGUUAUUACAUUAUCUGCUGCCUGUACCUUUUCUAUUUUUACAAUUUUAAAAUAUAUUCUUAUCACUUCAUAUAUUUCUUCUUCCAUGAAAGAAAGAAGCAAAGGGGGAACUCUUUCCUCCCACCCCCUCUCCAAAUGCACUGUUUUCUUUUCAGUUCUCAAAAAGCCUAGUUGCUGACUAUUCUGCUCAUCCAUUCAUCUCGGUUAAACAUUCUGCCUCUGGUGAUGGUCUUUGUUUUCAUAUCUCCAUACUGUGAGGACAUUUUUUGGCCUGCAGAAAUUCACAAACCUUGCUCUGCCCCUCCCAAAGAGAGCAAUUUGAAUUUAAAAAAAAAUACUGGAUCUAAAUUUAACUAUCAACCACUAUGGAAUUAUUGUGUGCACUACUCUGAAGCUAGAAAGAGAAAACAGGCAGUAUUUUCAUAUAGAAAGGACUUUCUAACUAUAUCUGAAAAAAAUUAUUACAUUCCCUAAAAUAUGUAUACUUCAUGUUCUGCUUAAAACCUUUAAAAGAAAAGGGAAAGAGGAAACAUAUAGAAUAGUUCAUCUCAUAUAAAACAUAAGCAAUAGAUUUGGAUUCAGAAUUUUUUUACCUAGGGUACAGUGGAAAAAUCAGGGGGUAUAAUUCAUCCUAUGUCAGUUCUAAGUGAUUGGGAAAGAAUAGACCAAAAAGACUACAUUUCUACAGAAAGUGACAAAUAUAGAUAAAUUAUAAAGAAAUGUUCUCUAGCAGGUCUUAAUAGUGGCUCUAAUUUUAUAUAUAUAUAUAUAUUGAAUACAUUACAGAAAAUACCUGAGUAUAUGAAAAAUUUCUAUUAAUUGUUUCCAUAUUUGAGUUGUAGGAUUUUAACAAACUAAUUAAAUGUUGGUGUUAUGACCGCUUUAUAUAUACAUAUUUUCAACAUUAAUCAGUUUUUAAAGGUCUGGGGGAAAGUGAAAGAAACAAUUGCAUUGUUUUAGGCUGCAAGUUCUACUGACUGCUUCACAAAUGUUACCCCGUUUAUCUUGCAUAAACAUCACAAUGGAGUCGCUAUUAUUUUCUCCACUUAAUAGAUAAGUAAACAAAGUUCAGAAUGAUUUAAUAACUUAUCCUAUACUAUGCAACCAGUAAUAGAACUGAGUGUUAUGGAUCGUACUGAUUGCAAACCCAAGCUGCUUCUUAGCAGCUUUCUGCCCAAAACAUUACAAAUUUUAGCUCAACAGGGGUUAGACUCAACAUCCACAUGAUGGGGCAGAGUCUGGAACAAAACGGAGUUUACAGUAUUAUAGCCAAAGUCUUAACACCAGAAAGAAUACAUCCUGUAGCCAACCCAUCUUUGGAGGAUUCAUUACCACCUUUGGGAAGAGUAGAAACACUCACAUUAGCAGCAUCAUCAUUUUCCAAUAGUAACUCCCUCCUAAUGCCUGUCUGCAAAAUCACAUGGCCUCAUAAGGCAUUGCCCCAAAGGGACAAUCUGAACGAGAGACACCCUGCUGUUCUCAGUGAUCAUCUUACCUAUGAUUCUGGUCUUCUUUCUAUCAUUAGGUGUACCCACCUGUGUUCUUUACCUUUAUGAUGUGAUUAAUGCUUUUCCAGGAAGUGUCCCCAUCUCUCCUGUGUACAGAUCCGUGAUGGACCUACCUUACCAGUGCUCUAGGCUGCUAGGACUGAGAAAGGGGGAACCCAGCACAGGUGCAAGCUGAGAUGCUUGCUAUGUUAGAUUCACAUCUCAAUUGUGCUACAACUUGCUAAAUAGGUCUGCUUCUAGGAAUAAUAUAGCCUCCUCAAUCCUGAGUUUUAUUUUAGGUCAGAUGUGGCUAACAAGGUUUCAGCUAGGUGCCUUAUAUAACUUUUAUGAAUGCUAAAUGAAAGACUUUAUGUGACUCUGAUUUGAAGUGAUGUAUUUUUGUGAGAAGGAUAUAAGGACAAUGAAAAUGAAAAAUGAUUACAUAGUAAGACUAAGAGCUGGUAAAAUUCAUGACUAAACAACUAUAAAACUACAAAAUCCAAUUUUAUUUUAAUGAUUCAUAAAUUAUUAUGAUACUUACUGAACAAUGGAAGUUUCUCAAAAAAUCUCAGCUCUUUGUGUUUGCAACUUUCUGUGCCUGUCUUUGUUUUUAUUUGGUUGGUGAUAUUGGGGAAGGUCUCCACCAAAGGAGGUUGAAGGUUAGUACACAGGAGGUUGGGUAUGAAAUGGUGUUCAUUGUUCCUGCUAGUAGACAAAACUGUAAGAAGAAUCCUACAUAAAAUUUUACAUUCUCUAUAUAGCUUCAAUUCGAAAAGGAUUCUUGAGAUAGCAUCCAGAUAGGAAAUAUAUACAAAAAUAAUUAGUCCAUAGCUUUGUUACGUUCAUUCUCCUACCCACACACUAAGAAUUCUCAUCAACUGUGUAUCUAGAAUAGCUCCUCUAGGAAAUCUCAGUCUCUGUAUGUAGAGAUAGAAACUCACCCUGGUGACACCUUGUUAGUUGGCUGAAAUUUUGGCACUCAUAGUAGCCAACUCCUUAUAUUGGUCUCCCUGGCCUUACUAUUGCCCUGGAUACUAAUCAUAUUAGGAAAGAAAUAUAUAGAUGAGCAAAUAAAUGAGUGCAUAGCCAUAAAUAAUUUUUGAAAUGACUGUGUUUCCAUAGCCCGGAAAAAAGGAGGAAUAAAGCAAACAGGAUAAUUGUCUUCAUAUGUCCCAUCGAGAAUCUUGCAGGAGGCAAACAUAGUUGUUUAUUGCCUUCCACAAAGUGGGGAAAAAUACCCUAGAAUCAAAAAGUAGGUUUACAUAAAAGUGGAAUUAACAUCAAUAUGAGAAAAUAUUUUUGAACAUUAUAAGUUAUGCAACAAUGAGGUCUUGUGAAUUAUUGUGCAGCCUUACUAUAAAUAGAAACAUAAAGGUUGAGUAAAAUAUAAAUACGUUGAACAGGCAUUUGCAAUAGAGUCUUUCCAAUGUCUCUUCAAUCUUGAAAAUUUAAGAUUUCAUAAUAAACUUUUUCAUCUUUUUAAUGAGGGGCGGAGUUUAACCUGAUUUUAAACAAACUUACAGUCAUUUAAAGAUUUUUAAAUGGUAAUUCUAAGAUAAUCUUUUUUCUGUCAAAAUCCCGUCUUGUUCUUCCGAGGAUUCAGCAGAGUCAUCAAAAGAAAAUAUUCAAGUAGGAAAAAAUUGUUGUAUAAGCUUCAUACUUGUGGUUCUCAUACUUUUAUUCCCACAAUGCCAUCACAACUUUAUUUCUAGAUAUACAUGGUUUCACAUUUUAAAAUAUUAGCCUGAUAUUCAGUGAUAGUGGCUCAAUGACUUUUGCCUUAAACACAGGCACAGGGGCUUGCACAUGUAAUCCCAAAAACUGAAGAGAUUGAGGUGGGAGGAUCGCUUGAGCCCCGUAGUUUGAGGCUGCAGUGAGCUAUGACCAUGCUACUGCAUUCCAGCCUGGGCAACAGAGUGGGACCCCAUCUUUGAAAAAACAAACAAACAAACAAACAAAAAACCCCACAGAGCAGUGACAGAUUAAACCACAAGGAGAGGAAAUGAAAAAGACAAAAUUAGCCCCCAAGGCAAGAUAAACAUCUCUGUGGAUCAGAAACAAAACAUAAAAUCAGAUGUGUGAGUGAUGCAGAAGCCACGGGUUAGCCGACUGUUUGUAAGCUGGCCUGAGUGGAGAUAGCUUUGCUCUUAGGAACUAAAUAUAUUAAAGUUCUUCAUGCAAUAAUGGGGAACUGAGGCUUAGCACCUUCCUUGAAAAUAAGGUAUGGAGGAGGGUGGGAGGGACUGACUUCCUUUGCUUACUAAUGAAGACCAAAAAAUGUACUGUGCUGUACUGCUUCCCUAUGUAGCUAGCUGAAGACUUGUGAGAACCCAGGCCCUGCGCUGCAACCAAAUGUGGAAUCCAGACACCCACUCUGGGUGCUGGGAUUCCCAAUAUACUCAGUCUCACUAUAGGUACAUAAUUCUAAACCAUUUACGUAAGAUCCAGGUCUGGAUAGGAAGCCCAAAGAGCUGGGCCAAGACAACCCCUGAGCUUCUAGAUGAGAGAAGAGGGAGGGAGAGAGACAGACAGAGAGAAAUGGAGAGAGAACUGGGUUUUUAAAUCUAUUUUCAGAAGCUGCCAAGAGAAGCAGCCCAAAAUAUCAACAACUGGAAAAUAAAUUCACUUCUGAUGAUGUCCCUUGUGCAUGUUCAGGAAUGAACAAUUGAUAAAUAUUUAUGUUUAUGUUUAAAUGCAUAAAAGAUUUCUUAAAGAUAUGCUAACUAUUUUAGAUGGCCAGGGAUUAAGACGGAAAAUAAUUAGAAAAUAACAGAUGGAUCCCAAAAGAUAACAAUUACAGAGCUUAGAAAUAAAACACGCAUUCCCUGAAAUAAGGACUAACUCUUGUUUUUUUUUUUUUUUUUUUUGAGACGGAGUCUCGCUCUGUCGCCCAGGCUGGAGUGCAGUGGCACAAUCUCGGUUCACUGCAAGCUCUGCCUCCUGGUUUCAUGCCAUUCUCCUGCCUCAGCCUCCCGAGUAGCUGGGACUACAGGCGUCUGCCACCAUGCCCGGCUAAUUUUUUGCAUUUUUAGUAGAGACGGGGUUUCACUGUGUUAGCCAGGAUGGUCUCGAUCUGCUGACCUCGUGAUCCACCCACCUCGGCCUCCCAAAGUGCUGGGAUUACAGGCGUGAGCCACCGCGCCCGGCCAACUCUUCUUAAAUAUGAAAAAAAUUCAACUAACAGGAUAAAUUCUAGAUGGAGUACAUUAUGGGAAAAAAUGUGAAAUAGAACAUGGAAUGCAUAAUUUUCCCAAAAUGCAACAGAGACUAUUUUUUAAGAAAAUGGAAUAAAAAGCACAUAGAAUCUAGACUCAGAUAUAAUAUCUAUUUAUUUUAUAAGGACGUAAAAAUAAUGAUGAAAAUAGGAUAGGACAUUAUUGCUGAAAUUUUUUUCCUGAUGGCUAAACACAUGAAUUCUCAGAACAAAAGAUACUCUGAGUAUCAAGCUACAUGAAUAAAAAUAAAUUAAUAUCUAGACAUAUCAUAAUGAAAGCACAGAACAUUAAGGAGGAAAAGAAAAUAAUAAAACCUUCAGAGAAUAAAAGAAUAGCUACAAAAGAAUAACAAAUAAUAGUGGACUUCCCCUCAGCAAAACAGAUGCCAAAAGAGAAUAUUCAAAAGGAUUAGGAAAACUGUUACUCUACAAUUUCACACACAGUUAAACUGUAAUUCAAGAAAAAGAGAAAAAUGAAAAUGUUUUCAAACAAAGUCUAAGGAAAAUUACCUCCCUUAGGUCUUCAACAGAAUUAUUAAUAAAUAUAUUGGAUAGAAAAAAAGAUGAAAACAGAAUAAAAGUAUAUAGGGUACAUGCGAAGCAUACGAGUUGAUAAAGAAUAAUAGUAAAUAUAAUUGUUGAAUGUAAACAAAAUAGCUUUUUAUAUGAAAUAAUAAAAGCUCUUAGCAGCUGUAACAGGUUGAUGUAAAUAAUACCAAUGAAUAAUUAAAUCACGGUAAAGCUCUUGACUUGACUAGAAAGGUGAAAAUGCUGAAUAAUUGUAGAUUGCAUUAGAAAAAUUUAUAAUUUAGUGUGUGUUAAAAAUUCAAAAGUAGAUCACAUUUGCCAUCUUUGAGCCCCCCACCUCUGCUGCAGUUGUAGCAGGCAAUACGUCUGUCAUCCACUCCUCAGUGGCUUCACCAGCCUUUCAGCCAGAUACAAGGCUGUUGUCCUAGUGAUUACAGCCACAUGAGUCACUGGUCAGCUCAGCGGCUAUCCCGACCUGCUGCCUGACUCCCAUAAUCUUCACCCAUUUAUGAGUGAGAACAUGCAAUAUUUGUCUUUCUGUGCCUGGCUUGUUUCACUUAAGAUAAUGAUCUCUAGUUUCAUCCAUCUUGUUGUAAAAUACAUAAUUUCAUAGUUUUUUAAUGGCUGAAUAGUAUUCCAUUACAUAUGUAUAAUACUUUUUUUUAUACUUUCAUUUAUUGAUGGACACAUGUUGUAUUAGUCUGUUCUCAUGCUGCUAAUAAAGACAUACCUGAGACUGGGCAAUUUAUUUUUAAAACAGGGUUUAGUUGACUCACAGUUCAGCAUGGCUGAGGAGGCCUCAGGAAACUUACAAUCAUGGCGGAAGUGGAAGCAAACACAUCCUUCUUCACACGGUGGCCAGAAGAACUGCCAAGCAAAGCAGGGAAAGCCUUUUAAAAAACCAUCAGAUCAGCCUGGCAUGGUGACUCACACCUGUAAUCCCAGCACUUUGGGAGGCCGAGGUGGGUGGAUCGCGAGAUCAGGAGUUCAAGACAAGCCUGGCCAAUAUGGUGAAACCCCAUCUCUUCUAAAAUACAAAAAUUACCGGGCAUGGUGGCACGUGCUUGUAGUCCCAGCUACCUGGGAGGCUGAGGCAGAAGAAUCGCUUGAACCCAGGAGGCGGAGGUUGCAGUGAGCC